GCUCAGUGAGACUUUCCUGUCACUGGCUACUACUACUCCCAACCCUCCUCAAAGCCGCCGGAGCAACCCCCAGGUCUUUACUUUACAAUCGGCAAUUUGACUUGCUCUGCUGCAUGUCUGGAGGGACCAAGGAAAGUGUGGAGACGCUCCAAGGAUUAGGUGAUCGGAGCUUGAAAAGAAAAAAAGCCAAACAAAUAAACAAAACCCACCCACCCUAACAAAUAUGAGGCUGCUGGAGAGAAUGAGGAAAGACUGGUUCAUGGUCGGAAUAGUGCUGGCGAUCGCUGGAGCUAAACUGGAGCCGUCCAUAGGGGUGAAUGGGGGACCACUGAAGCCAGAAAUAACUGUAUCCUACAUUGCUGUUGCAACAAUAUUCUUUAACAGUGGACUAUCAUUGAAAACAGAGGAGCUGACCAGUGCUUUGGUGCAUCUAAAACUGCAUCUUUUUAUUCAGAUCUUUACUCUUGCAUUCUUCCCAGCAACAAUAUGGCUUUUUCUUCAGCUUUUAUCAAUCACACCCAUCAACGAAUGGCUUUUAAAAGGUUUGCAGACAGUAGGUUGCAUGCCUCCGCCUGUGUCUUCUGCAGUGAUUUUAACCAAGGCAGUUGGUGGAAAUGAGGCAGCUGCAAUAUUUAAUUCAGCCUUUGGAAGUUUUUUGAUGGACAGAGUGAAGAUAAAAGACAACUGUAGAGAUAACAGCGUACUUCACAGCUGACUGAAGCAGGUGUUAGAAAUGCAGAUGAAGUGUAUUGACUAAAGACUAUACAAAUUCGAAGUGAAAAUGCCACUGGUCUGCAUGCAGUGUUCUGCACAUAUGAAGUUUCAGGUAGUUAAAUUAUUCAUUUUAUUGUGUGAAAUAGUUGAGGAGUUAGGGAAAAGGUGCCUUUUACAUUUAAACUGUUAUUUCCCUUCUUCCUUUCAUCUGCACUUGACAAGCAAAACGAGCUUCAUUAUGUAAGUUUUAUUCCAGCAAAUGCAUGACUUACAUCUCUAUAUUUUAAAAAGUACACCAAGAAACAGAUCACCUAUAGGCUUCAGUGACAGUAUAAAACAAGAGAAACUAAAAAUUAUUUUUCUUCUUCACUUUUAAUAUAAUGAAAACACUAAAGACGAAUGUGAAAGUAGCUAUUUAAUCAUCAUUGCUAUCACCCUCACCAUGAAUUAUUUUUCAAGUGCCUAUAUGUACAUUACUCUCCUUCAAACAUUAGUAUUAAUUGUAUACAUUAGUAACACUAAUACUACAUUAAUACUAAUUGUAAACAUUAGUAUUAAUUAGCAUACACCUCCUUCAAACAUUAGUAUUAAUUGUAUGGGUUAGAAGAGUUUAAAAAAUAAGCCAUUCCUUCUGUCUUAUAAUUCAAAAGUCCUGAGUAUUUUAUUUAAAGACAAAACAGAUAUUUAAAAAUAUUUAAUAUGGAAUUUUAAAGCAGAGUCUUAUUUUAAGGGAAAUGUCACAAUUCCUGGAAUUAUUUCUUGUCUUAUUUGGCUCAUUUUGUUUUUCCAUCUCAUAGUCUGGCUGACUUUGCUAUAGGGCACCACGGUGGUCUGUAGAGGUUGACAUGAGUAUAAAAAUACCUGCUUUUGGGAAACUCAGAUGACUUCAAGACACUUAAGGAAGUUUGACACAUAUUUAAAAGGAAAACAGAAGCAAUCCUCAUUUUAAAGGUGAAGAAGGCCGGGCAAGGUGGCUUACACCUGUAAUCCCAGUACUUUGGGAGUCCAGAGCAGGUGAAUCAUCUGAGUCAGGAGUUCGAAACCAGCCUGGCCAAAAUGGUGAAACCCCAUCUUUACUAAAAAAAACAGUACAAAAAUUAGCCAGGCGUGGUGGCUCAUGUAAUUCCAAUUACUCGGGAGGUUGAGGCAGGAGAAUUGCUUGAACUGGAGAGGCGGAGGUUGCAGUGAGCCGAGAUCAUGCCAUUGCACUCCAGCCUGGGUGACAGAGCAAGACUCUGUCUCAAAAUAAAUACAUAAAUAAAGGUGAAGAAACUAUGAACAAGAUAUGCCUUAAAAGAUCUUUUAAAACAAUCUUCAUUAAGAUUCAAGGUUAUGGAACUACUGAAAUUUUGACUCAAUGUACAAGUGUGUAGGUUUAAAAUAUUUUUCUUUUGGCUCUUAGGACAAAGGGCUUCAGAAUCCAACAGGCUUGGAUUGUAAUCCAUGCUUGGAUGAAUGCUAGUUUAUCCAUCCUUGAUAAACUAGGUAACUUUGGACAACUUAUUAGCCUUGAUCCAAAUUUCUCUAAAUGUAAAAUGAGGAUAAUAAUAAUACCUAUUCUUAGGGAUCUUUGUGAUAUUAAAUUUAAAACAGUCGGCCUGGCUCAUUGUAGGAAGUCUAUGUGUGUCUACUUUCCUUUUUAUUAGAGCAGUAGCUUUCCUUGCCUAAAAUCCUGCCUGUGCUAUAUUCUCAUUUUAAUUUAAUAGGACCAUUUUAAAAGCUGUAGAGCUGCAUUUGAGUGUUGAUAUAGACUUUUUGUCAGUUUUAGUUGGCUUUGUAGUUUGAGAUUUGGGGAAGAGUUUUGAGAUAUAUUGUCUUUAAUUGGCAGACUGAUAUAGGGAGGAAAUUAUUAGAUUUGGGAUCAGAAUAUCUUAGUUUAUUUCCUGACUAUUAAUACUAAUGUUAGAACUGUAGACAAAUCAUCUAACUUAUUAGGCCUCUAUGUUCUCAUCUAUAUAGUGGAGAAAAAUAAUACUACCUUACCUUUCUAACCUUGUUGGAUUACUGUGAGAAUCAGAUGAUAUAAUGUGUGAGAGAUACUUUGUGAUUAUUAAAUGUCCUUAAAAACUAAGUAAACUAUUAACAUCUGCAAUUUAUCAUUAUUGAAUAUAUCAUGUGUGUCUCCUUCCCAUUGGAAGGUACAAUUAUGCUAUGAAAUGUUAAGAUUAAUUGCUUAUUUCCACAGCAAAGGAUAUCACUUUUUGUGAUCACUUACUAGUAAAUUAAGCCAAAUAAUUUGCUAACUCAGUUAUGAAAUUGAUCCCAUUAAAAGUAAACACAUAACUAUCCAACACAGCAUUAAUUCUACCAUAUACAUUUAUAGCUUAAAAAUUUAUGUAAUAUAUAGGACAACGGCUCUAUUUCUCACGUUCUUGAUUAGUUACCACAGCAUGGCUUAACCCAGCAUAAAAUAACUCUUGGUUCUUAUCAGUUCACAGAUGUGCUAUUCCCCGAUUUUAAAAUUAAGGUAUAAUUUACAUAGAGUAAAAUUCAUCCUUUUUUAGUAUACAGUUCUGUAAGUUUUGAUAAUUGUUUAAUAUAUAAUGACCACUAUAAUCAAGAUGUAGAACAUUCCAUCACCCCCAAAGUUUCCCUGUGCCCUUUUGUAGGCAAUGCCUCUAUCCCCCUCCCUCCCAGCCCUUGGCAACCACUGAUCUGUUUUUUUAUCCCUUUAGUUUUGCCUUUUCCAGAACACCCUAUACAUUGAAUCAUACAAUAUGUACUUUUUUGAGUUUGACAGUGUGGCUUUUUUUUUUUUUGAUGUGCCAUAUUCAAUAGCAUUUUUUUUCUAUUUGGAAGCAAAAGUGUUAUUGCACUUACUUUUUAGAAGAGAUUUCCAAAGUUGCAUUUUUUUUGGAGUGUGCUUUUUAUUUACUGAGAAACACUGGUUGAUGUUUUUGACUUCUAUGUUUAUAGAUAGCUUGAGAGUACCUAAGUAUUCCCAAGCCUUUGCCUAUACAUACCCAUUAAAAAAUUUCUCCUUCUAUGUUUCCUAUAUAUUGCAAACAAAGUUAAAUUACCUUUCAGAAUAUCUGAAAUAUAUUUGUUCCCCCAUUUUCGGUUCAGAGUUUUUGUUUUUUAAUAACUAUAACCCUUGAAUGUGUGAAUUUACUAUGCCUCUUGGAAUUUCCACUUAGCUGCUGGAUUAACAACCAGUACUGCCAUAAUAUGUUGAAAUUUCUAGGAGGCUGAAAUUCUGAGCCAUGAAGAAUGCAAUAGAAAUGAUUAACAUUAAAGCUGAUGUCACCCCACUAAGGCUUAAAGUGGUAUAGAUAUUAAUAGAUAAUAAAGCAUUAGAUAAUCUGAGAACAAGAGGGUUGAUAUUCCUACAAAGCUGAGAAUUAAAGGAUGCUUCAGAGAAAAAAAAUUGACUUAAAAUAUUCCCUCCAUUAGUGUCCACCAGUCAACUUUAUAUUGUUGAACAUCAGGCCCAAGAUCAACAAUUGUCUACUUCCCAUUUUCGAAGUAGUCAGUUGUUGGCCUUGAGUCUGAUGUUCAACAAUAUAAAGUCUCAAGCUCUUUCCAUCUCUCUGCUCCAUUAUUCUUAGCUGUUGGUAUUUUUUUUGUUUUGUUUUGUUUUGUUUUGUUUUUUGAGACACAGUCUUGCUCUGUCACUCCAGGGUUCAAGCAGUUCUUGUGUCUCACCCUCCCAAGUAGCCGGGACUAUAGGUGUGCACCACCACGCCCAGCUAAUUUUUUGUAUUUUAGUAGAGACAGAGUUUCACCAUGUUGCCCCCAGGGUGGUCUCAAACUCCUGAGCUCAGGCAAUCUGCCUGCCUCAUCCUCCCAAAAUGCUAAGAUCAUAGCUGUGAGCCACCGUGCCUGGCUAGCUGUUGGUCUUUUAUCCUCAUGCUUUGUUACUUCAUGGUAGUGAGAUGGCUGUUGAGGUUUUAGGCAUUGUAUUUUUGUUCGAGGUAGGAAGAAAGGGAAAAGGCACCGCUGAUAUGCUAUCCUGUUAUUUCUGUCCUUUUAUAUGUUAGAACAAGCAUUUCCAGGAGGCUCUCAGCUGACUUUCCCUAAUGUUGCAUUGGCCAGAACUGGAUUACUGCUAGCUGUAAGGAGAGGAGAGAAAUUGAGUAUCUAUCCAAGGGAACAGAAUUUGGCUUAGAAACGUGCUUCCUGACUGACGUUUUUCCCUUUAUGGCACGUGUAGGAAAUGAUAACAUUUGUUGUACAUCCUGAGGGUGAACAGAAUGCUUCUGCUAAUCUAGGCCCAGUCCUUCUGCCCUGAGAGUUAAGGGGAAUCAAUAUCUCGGCUAUCUGUCAUGUAUUUGAGGCACAUAUUACUUGGAAAUGUGACUGGUUUAGACUAACUAGACUAACAGUGAGUCAUAUCCUAGAUUGGGCAUAUUGUUGUCCCAAAGAAAACAGGGUUCUGUUAACAUAUAAGAGGGUGGGAAUGGCUAUAAAGUAGGCAGUUAAUAGUCUGGCACAGUAGCUGUUUGUUUAAAGAUUAUCUUCAAUUUUAGAAUAUGCUGUAUCUGGAUUUGAAUAAAUACGUAUUUGUUACUCUCAGAAGUCACCUUUUCCCCCUUUAAUAAUGAAACUUCUGGAAUGUGGGGGAAAUGGUUGUUCAGUGUAUAUAAAGUUUUAAUUAUCUGCUAAAGUUCUAGAAAUCUUUUGUACAACAUAAUGCCUAUGCUUGAUAAUACAGUAUUGUGUACUUCAGAAUUUGUAAAGAGCGUAGAUCUCAUGUUACAUGUUCUUAUUACAAAGAGCAACAAUGGGAUACAAGGAAACACUGAGAAAUAUUGCAUGUGUCCGUUAACUUGAUUGUGGUGAUGGUAUCAUGGGUGUUUUCAAUGUUCAAACUCAUAAAAUUGUACACAUUAAAUAUAUGCAGUUAUUUGUAUAUCAAUUAUACCUCAAUAAAACUGCUUAAAUAUUGUGAAAGAG